GCAGGCCUGGCGAGGCGGCGGCGGGCGGAGGCUGGGCCGGAGGGGUGGGGACGGCGAGGAGGUGGAGGCCGGCGCUCCGCUCCGCUCCAGCUCGGUUUCAUGUCCCGCCAGGCGAAGGAUGACUUCCUGCGGCACUACACAGUGUCGGACCCCAGGACUCACCCCAAGGGCUACACCGAGUACAAAGUAACCGCGCAGUUCAUCUCAAAGAAGGACCCAGAGGAUGUCAAAGAGGUGGUGGUCUGGAAGCGGUACAGCGACUUCCGCAAGCUGCAUGGAGACCUGGCCUACACCCACCGCAACCUCUUCCGCCGCCUCGAGGAGUUCCCUGCUUUCCCCCGGGCCCAGGUGUUUGGCCGGUUUGAAGCCUCAGUGAUCGAGGAGCGGCGAAAGGGGGCAGAGGACCUGCUUCGCUUCACUGUGCACAUACCUGCGCUCAACAACAGCCCCCAGCUCAAGGAGUUCUUCCGGGGUGGGGAGGUGACCCGACCCUUGGAGGUGUCCAGGGACCUACACAUCCUGCCACCCCCUCUGAUCCCCACCCCGCCCCCUGAUGACCCCCGGCUAUCCCAACUGCUCCCUGCAGAAAGGAGGGGCCUCGAGGAAUUGGAGGUGCCAGUGGACCCCCCACCAUCCAGCCCUGCCCAGGAGGCCCUGGAUCUCCUCUUUAACUGUGAGAGCACCGAGGAGGCAUCUGGUUCCCCUGCCCGAGGCCCCCUCACCGAGGCUGAGCUUGCCCUCUUCGACCCCUUCUCCAAGGAAGAAGGCGCAGCCCCCAGCCCCACCCAUGUGGCUGAGCUGGCAACGAUGGAGGUGGAGUCUGCAAGGCUGGACCAGGAACCCUGGGAGCCAGGAGGGCAGGAGGAGGAAGAGGAUGGGGAAGGAGGGCCCACCCCUGCCUACCUAAGCCAGGCCACAGAGCUCAUCACCCAGGCCCUGCGGGAUGAGAAGGCAGGCGCUUACGCUGCUGCACUCCAGGGCUAUCGAGACGGCGUGCACGUCUUGCUUCAGGGAGUCCCCAGUGACCCGUUGCCUGCCCGCCAGGAAGGUGUGAAGAAGAAGGCAGCUGAGUACCUGAAGCGGGCAGAGGAGAUCCUGCGCCUGCACCUGUCUCAACUCCCACCCUAACAGGGAGUGGGCCAUUCCCUGGGACUCUCGCUCCUGCACUGCCAGCCCCUUCUCCUCUCCCCAGGGCCUGGCCCUACCUCCUGGUCUUGUAAUUACAGGAGCCAUUUCUGUAGGUAACUGGACCAAGAAUGAGAAAAAUAAUGAAUUCUUAGCUCCCUGAUUACACCUGCCACCUUGGAAUCAAGGACUCACACUUCUGACCCUGCCUGUCUUUUUGGGGUUUUUUUGAGUUGGAGUCUCGCUGUGUCGCCCAGACUGGAGUGCAGUGGUGGGAUCGCGGCUCACUGCAACCUCCACCUCCCAGGUUCAAGCAGUUCUCCUGUCUCAGCCUCCCCAGUAGCUGAGAUUGCAGGCACAUGCCACCACGCCCAGCUAAUAUUUUGUAUUUUCAGUAGGGACGGGGUUACACCAUGUUGGCCAGGCUGGUCUCGAACUCCUGACCUCAAGUGAUCCACCCGCCUCAGUCUCCCAAAGUGCUGAGAUUACAGGCAUGAGUCACUACGCCCGGCCCAUGUCUGUCUGUCUUGAUGUGUGAGCAGCAGCUGUGGUCAUUAAACCAUUAGUUUACCCCUCUAGAACUGGGGUCUGCAAACUCCCACCUGCAGCCAAAUCUGGCCCACCUCCUUUUUAAUGUAAGGGCUGUGAGAGUGGUUUUUACUUUUUUUAAUGAUUAAAAAAAUCAAAAUAAUAUUCUGUGACAAUGACAGGUGAAAUUUAUAUGUGACAAGUGAAAAUUAUAUGAAAUUUAAGAGUCCAUAAAUAAAAUUUGUUGGAACACAA